CAAACUAGGACUUGCUCAGCAGAGGCCGCCAGCCCGGAGCUGGAUCCAGAGCCCGGCCUUGGGGACCCCAGCUCCCACCUGCGCCCUGCCUUCCAGAUCAGCCAACCGCCUGCCAUGGAGACUUUCUUUAGGAGACAUUUCCGGGGGAAGGUGCCAGGCCCUGGAGAGGGGCAGCAGCGGCCCAGCAGCGUGGGGCUGCCCACAGGCAAGGCCCGGCGUCGCUCCCCCGCUGGGCAGGCCUCCUCCUCACUGGCACAGCGGCGCCGCUCCAGCGCCCAGCUCCAGGGCUGCCUCCUGAGUUGCGGGGUGAGGGCCCAGGGUUCCAGCCGCCGGCGCUCCAGCACUGUGCCCCCUUCCUGCAACCCCCGCUUCAUCGUGGAUAAGGUGCUCACUCCACAGCCUACCACCGUGGGGGCCCAGCUUCUGGGUGCACCCCUGCUGUUGACCGGGCUUGUGGGCAUGAAUGAGGAGGAGGGUGUCCAGGAGGAUGUGGUAGCCGAGGCAUCGAGCGCCAUCCAGCCAGGCACCAAGACACCAGGGCCACCCCCACCUCGGGGCGCCCAGCCGCUGUUGCCCCUACCCCGCUACCUGCGCCGAGCCUCCUCCCACCUGCUCCCCGCGGAUGCCGUAUAUGACCACGCUCUCUGGGGCCUGCACGGCUACUAUCGGCGCCUCAGCCAGCGGCGGCCCUCAGGCCAGCACCCUGGCCCUGGGGGCCGAAGAGCCUCAGGCACCACCGCCGGCACCAUGCUGCCCACCCGUGUGCGCCCACUGUCCCGCAGGCGCCAGGUAGCCCUACGGCGCAAGGCGGCCGGACCCCAGGCCUGGAGCGCCCUGCUCGCGAAAGCCAUCACCAAGUCGGGCCUCCAGCACCUGGCCCCCCCUCCGCCCACCCCUGGGGCCCCGUGCAGCGAGUCAGAGCGGCAGAUCCGGAGUACAGUGGACUGGAGCGAGUCAGCGACAUAUGGGGAGCACAUCUGGUUCGAGACCAACGUGUCCGGGGACUUCUGCUACGUUGGGGAGCAGUACUGUGUAGCCAGGAUGCUGAAGUCAGUGUCUCGAAGAAAGUGCGCAGCCUGCAAGAUUGUGGUGCACACGCCCUGCAUCGAGCAGCUGGAGAAGAUAAAUUUCCGCUGUAAGCCGUCCUUCCGUGAAUCAGGCUCCAGGAAUGUCCGCGAGCCAACCUUUGUACGGCACCACUGGGUACACAGACGACGCCAGGACGGCAAGUGUCGGCACUGUGGGAAGGGAUUCCAGCAGAAGUUCACCUUCCACAGCAAGGAGAUUGUGGCCAUCAGCUGCUCGUGGUGCAAGCAGGCAUACCACAGCAAGGUGUCCUGCUUCAUGCUGCAGCAGAUCGAGGAGCCGUGCUCGCUGGGGGUCCACGCAGCCGUGGUCAUCCCGCCCACCUGGAUCCUCCGCGCCCGGAGGCCCCAGAAUACUCUGAAAGCAAGCAAGAAGAAGAAGAGGGCAUCCUUCAAGAGGAAGUCCAGCAAGAAAGGGCCUGAGGAGGGCCGCUGGAGACCCUUCAUCAUCAGGCCCACCCCCUCCCCGCUCAUGAAGCCCCUGCUGGUGUUUGUGAACCCCAAGAGUGGGGGCAACCAGGGUGCAAAGAUCAUCCAGUCUUUCCUCUGGUAUCUCAAUCCCCGACAAGUCUUCGACCUGAGCCAGGGAGGGCCCAAGGAGGCGCUGGAGAUGUACCGCAAAGUGCACAACCUGCGGAUCCUGGCGUGCGGGGGCGACGGCACGGUGGGCUGGAUCCUCUCCACCCUGGACCAGCUACGCCUGAAGCCGCCACCCCCUGUUGCCAUCCUGCCCCUGGGUACUGGCAACGACUUGGCCCGAACCCUCAACUGGGGUGGGGGCUACACAGAUGAGCCUGUGUCCAAGAUCCUCUCCCACGUGGAGGAGGGGAACGUGGUACAGCUGGACCGCUGGGACCUCCACGCUGAGCCCAACCCCGAGGCAGGGCCUGAGGACCGAGAUGAAGGCGCCACCGACCGGUUGCCCCUGGAUGUCUUCAACAACUACUUCAGCCUGGGCUUUGACGCCCACGUCACCCUGGAGUUCCACGAGUCUCGAGAGGCCAACCCAGAGAAAUUCAACAGCCGCUUUCGGAAUAAGAUGUUCUACGCCGGGACAGCUUUCUCUGACUUCCUGAUGGGCAGCUCCAAGGACCUGGCCAAGCACAUCCGAGUGGUGUGUGAUGGAAUGGACUUGACUCCCAAGAUCCAGGACCUGAAACCCCAGUGUGUUGUUUUCCUGAACAUCCCCAGGUACUGUGCGGGCACCAUGCCCUGGGGCCACCCUGGGGAGCACCACGACUUUGAGCCCCAGCGGCAUGACGACGGCUACCUCGAGGUCAUUGGCUUCACCAUGACGUCGUUGGCCGCGCUGCAGGUGGGCGGACACGGCGAGCGGCUGACGCAGUGUCGCGAGGUGGUGCUCACCACAUCCAAGGCCAUCCCGGUGCAGGUGGAUGGCGAGCCCUGCAAGCUUGCAGCCUCACGCAUCCGCAUCGCCCUGCGCAACCAGGCCACCAUGGUGCAGAAGGCCAAGCGGCGGAGCGCCGCCCCCCUGCACAGCGACCAGCAGCCGGUGCCAGAGCAGUUGCGCAUCCAGGUGAGUCGCGUCAGCAUGCACGACUAUGAGGCCCUGCACUACGACAAGGAGCAGCUCAAGGAGGCCUCUGUGCCGCUGGGCACUGUGGUGGUCCCAGGAGACAGUGACCUAGAGCUCUGCCGUGCCCACAUUGAGAGACUCCAGCAGGAGCCCGAUGGUGCUGGAGCCAAGUCCCCGACAUGCCAGAAACUGUCCCCCAAGUGGUGCUUCCUGGACGCCACCACUGCCAGCCGCUUCUACAGGAUCGACCGAGCCCAGGAGCACCUCAACUAUGUGACUGAGAUCGCACAGGAUGAGAUUUAUAUCCUGGACCCUGAGCUGCUGGGGGCAUCGGCCCGGCCUGACCUCCCAACCCCCACUUCCCCUCUCCCCACCUCACCCUGCUCACCCACGCCCCGGUCACUGCAAGGGGAUGCUGCACCCCCUCAAGGUGAAGAGCUGAUUGAGGCUGCCAAGAGGAACGACUUCUGUAAGCUCCAGGAGCUGCACCGAGCUGGGGGCGACCUCAUGCACCGAGACGAGCAGAGUCGCACGCUCCUGCACCACGCAGUCAGCACUGGCAGCAAGGAUGUGGUCCGCUACCUGCUGGACCACGCCCCCCCAGAGAUCCUUGAUGCGGUGGAGGAAAACGGGGAGACCUGUUUGCACCAAGCAGCGGCCCUGGGCCAGCGCACCAUCUGCCACUACAUCGUGGAGGCCGGGGCCUCGCUCAUGAAGACAGACCAGCAGGGCGACACUCCCCGGCAGCGGGCUGAGAAGGCUCAGGACACCGAGCUGGCCGCCUACCUGGAGAACCGGCAGCACUACCAGAUGAUCCAGCGGGAGGACCAGGAGACGGCUGUGUAGCGGGCCGCCCACGGGCAGCAGGAGGGACAAUGCGGCCAGGGGACGAGCGCCUUCCUUGCCCACCUCACUGCCACAUUCCAGUGGGACGGCCACGGGGGGACCUAGGCCCCAGGGAAAGAGCCCCAUGCCGCCCCCUAAGGAGCCGCCCAGACCUAGGGCUGGACUCAGGAGCUGGGGGGGCCUCACCUGUUCCCCUGAGGACCCCGCCGGACCCGGAGGCUCACAGGGAACAAGACACGGCUGGGUUGGAUAUGCCUUUGCCGGGGUUCUGGGGCAGGGCGCUCCCUGGCCGCAGCAGAUGCCCUCCCAGGAGUGGAGGGGCUGGAGAGGGGGAGGCCUUCGGGAAGAGGCUUCCUGGGCCCCCUGGUCUUCGGCCGGGUCCCCAGCCCCCGCUCCUGCCCCACCCCACCUCCUCCGGGCUUCCUCCCGGAAACUCAGCGCCUGCUGCACUUGCCUGCCCUGCCUUGCUUGGCACCCGCUCCGGCGACCCUCCCCGCUCCCCUGUCAUUUCAUCGCGGACUGUGCGGCCUGGGGGUGGGGGGCGGGACUCUCACGGUGACAUGUUUACAGCUGGGUGUGACUCAGUAAAGUGGAUUUUUUUUUC